GAAAAGGAAGAGCUUAAAAAGUCUGUACAGACAGCUUCAUGCAAAUCCCUAAAGAUGGAGAGCAAACUAAAAGAGAAAAAUCAAAUGUGACUACAAUAAUGGAAUUUGUUCUUUUGGGGUUUUCUGAUAUUCCCAAUCUCCACUGGAUGCUUUUUAGUAUAUUUUUACUUAUGUAUUUGAUGAUCCUGAUGUGCAAUGGCAUCAUAAUACUACUAAUAAAAAUUCACCCCGCUCUCCAGACUCCCAUGUAUUUUUUUCUUAGCAAUUUUUCCCUUUUGGAAAUCUGUUAUGUAACAAUCAUUAUCCCAAGAAUGCUCAUGGACAUUUGGACUCAGAAAGGAAAUAUUUCUUUGUUUGCUUGUGCUACACAAAUGUGUUUUUUUCUUAUGCUUGGAGGCACGGAGUGUCUCCUUCUGACAGUGAUGGCCUAUGACCGCUACGUGGCUAUUUGUAAGCCUUUGCAGUAUCCUCUAGUGAUGAACCACAAAGUCUGCAUUCAGCUGAUAAUAGCUUCCUGGACCAUCACAAUUCCUGUAGUAAUUGGGGAAACAUGCCAAAUUUUCCUUUUGCCCUUUUGCGGAACUAACACAAUUAAUCAUUUCUUUUGUGACAUCCCGCCAAUACUCAAGCUUGCUUGUGGAAACAUAUUUGUGAAUGAGAUAACAGUCCAUGUAGUAGCGGUGGUGUUUAUCACGGUGCCAUUUCUGUUGAUUGUUGUCUCUUAUGGCAAAAUUAUCUCCAACAUUUUGAAAUUGUCAUCAGCCAGAGGAAAGGCUAAAGCCUUCUCCACCUGCUCAUCUCACCUAAUAGUUGUAAUCUUAUUCUUUGGAGCAGGUACUAUCACUUAUUUACAGCCCAAACCACAUCAGUUUCAAAGGAUGGGGAAACUGAUUUCUCUUUUCUACACCAUUCUGAUUCCAACUUUGAAUCCUAUUAUAUAUACCCUGAGGAACAAAGAUAUCAUGGUGGCAUUGAGAAAAUUACUAGCUAAGUUAUUAACAUGAGAUGAAGACUUGAAAUUACAGAAAUAAUUUCUUUAUAGGUUUGUCAUGUGGCUUCAGUGAAUUUUUUUUUAACUUUGUCCCUAUGGUAUUCAAUAAUGAGUACUGAAAUUUAAAUACAAACUUACAUUAUGUCAAGGGGUGUUUUAUUCACAGAAUAUAGUUAUGUGCUACUGUGCAGUUGGAGCACAAUUUAACUAAGGUGCCAAGAUCUCAUUCUGAAGAUCAAUGGUUAACUGUUGAUUAAGAGACCACCUGAGCAAUAAAAUGAAAAAUAACUGAGUGAGUCAUAUAAUUAGGGGUUAGGAUCAGGCUCUGUAAUACAUCUUCUUUCACCUUCCCAUUCCUUCAGAUGUAUUUACCACCUUUCUCUGACCCUUGGGUUUGGAUUUAACUGAUUAGAAACACCAAAAAUAGCUAAGAUGGUGGAAACAAAGGAUAUGGGAUUUUCUUUGCAUUUUACCCUACUUGUUUCUCAUAUCUUUGUCCAUAUAUUUUUAAAUCUAAAUAUCCUGAGAAUGUUUAUUCCUCUAACUGCCUACAUCUUACUCGUCUCUGAUAACAUAUUUUCUUUCCUUGUAGCUUCAGGUCUUGCUUUGUUAAUAUUUAGUUUUCAUCCUAAACUAGCCUUACCUAUGUGUGUUGGGUUGAAUGUUGGACCCUCAAAAUAGAAAUCUCCAACUAGAACCUUCAAAUUUAAUCUUAUUUAGAAAAACAAAGACUUUCAGCUAUAGUGAAGCUAAAGAUUGUAAAUGAAAGUACCAUGAUUUAGGUUGCACAUGAAGUCCAACGACAAGUGUUAUUAUAAAAGACAAAGAGGCAGAAGAAGUUUGAGGGGAAAAAAGGUGCAGAGAAACAGAGAAGGACAUCAUGUAAAGGUGAAGGCAGAGACUGGAAUGAUUCAACCACAAACCAAAGAUGGUCAAGAUUCACCAAAACAAAAAGGGGCAAGGAAUGAGUCAUCCUUAAAGCCUUUGAAGGAAGUGAGUUCCUGCCAACGUUGUGAUUUUGGAGGAGCCUAGAGAACUGAUGAGUGACUAAUCUGCUAUUGCCUUAAGCCACCCAAUUUGCAGUAAGUUGUUAAGAUAAACCAGGGGAAAUAAUAUAUCACACAAAUUGUCCUCUUAUUUAAGUUUUUUAUUUGAAUAUCUGGAAUGAAUUCUGUAUUCCACCUUGCCUCAGCUGAUUCAGCUGAUAUGCCAUUCCACCCUACCCUUCAAUUGUUGCAUGCAUUUUGGGCAGUAAAUUGACUUCUGUUUAAAAAAAAAAAUAUAUAUAUAUAUAUAUAUAUUCUUCUUACUUUACAAGCUAAAUCAAUGAAAUUUGAUCUUGUAGAGGUAAUAUAUUUUCAAUAGUUAUUACAAACGUGUUUUUUCAAAAACUUUUAUAACGAAAUUUGUUUUAUUGAUGCAAAACAAAUUUGGGAGUAAAGGGAAGUCACUCUCAGAGUAUAUGAAGACACUGGAGUACAUCUUUACCUUACAGUAAUGCACAGCCUCUCAAGAUAAUGUCUCAGAACUGCUCAAUUGAAGAAAUUCCUACUUCCCUAAUAUGUAAGAAUGCAUAUGUACUUAAAAAAUAUAACAUCAUUUUUGUAAAACCAAUAAUAAUAGCAACUAUAAUUUCAUAUAGCAUUUUACAUGUGCAUAUUAGGAAUGGGAUGUUUGCAUAUUAGCAGUGUCUAGGAGGAUAUGCAUCAGAAGAGAAUAUUGGCUUCUUCAUACUGGCAAGAAUUCAGAAGAUUUCUGUUUUAUUAUAUUUUAAUUUACAAUUUAUAUUUACUACAUGGGGAAUAUAAAGUUAGAU